AGUCUGCUUUUCCCACAGCCUGAUGUCCAAGGGGCAGAUACGUGUGGUGGGCUUGCUGGAGAAAUAGGCUCUUCUCACGUGAGAACAGCAUCCUUCCAAUCUAGAGCUCCUGGCUCCAGGAAGUGGUGGUGGCUCUACCCUGGUGCUAUUUCAUUAGUGAAGGGUGGGGUGGUGGAAAGUGCAGAAAAGGCAGGACCCCUGACACCAGCAAGGCAUUGGAUCUCUCUGGACCUCCGGGUGGUGGACUUUGGGACUGGACAGACCUGGUCACAGUCUAGGUUCUACAUCUUACUGGUCGAGCAACUUUAGAGUCAACCUAUUUGAUUUCUUGACAAGACCACAAUCUGAUCCCAAAGAUGUGCUCCACAAAUCCAGGCAAAUGGGUCACCUUUGAUGAUGAUCCUGCUGUUCAAUCUUCUCAAAAGUCAAAGAAUUUUCCUCUGGAGAAUCAAGGUGUCUGUAGACCAAAUGGACUGAAGCUGAACCUUCCUGGCCUCAGGGAAUUUCCCAGUGGAUCUUCCUCCACCAGCAGCACUCCUCUCUCCUCCCCCAUUGUAGAUUUUUAUUUCAGUCCAGGACCUCCAAGUAACUCUCCUCUUUCUACACCUACCAAAGACUUCCCAGGUUUUCCUGGCAUCCCCAAAGCAGGGACUCAUGUGCUUUAUCCUAUUCCAGAAUCAUCUUCAGACAGCCCACUCGCAAUAUCAGGAGGAGAAUCUUCCUUACUGCCUACCAGACCAACAUGUUUAUCCCAUGCCUUGUUACCCAGUGACCACUCAUGUACACAUCCAACUCCCAAAGUAGGUCUUCCAGAUGAAGUUAAUCCUCAACAGGCUGAAAGCCUAGGAUUCCAAAGUGAUGAUCUCCCCCAGUUUCAGUAUUUUCGAGAGGACUGUGCUUUUUCAAGUCCAUUUUGGAAAGAUGAAGGCAGUGAUUCCCAUUUCACCCUUGACCCACCAGGAAGCAAAAAGAUGUUCUCAUCAAGAAACAAGGAGAUGCCUAUUGACCAAAAAAGCCUAAAUAAGUGUUCACUCAACUAUAUCUGUGAGAAGCUUGAACAUCUCCAGUCAGCUGAGAACCAAGACUCACUUAGAAGUUUGUCUAUGCACUGUCUAUGUGCUGAAGAAAAUGCCUCUUCCUUUGUCCCCCACACACUCUUCAGGAGUCAGCCAAAAUCCGGAUGGUCUUUCAUGCUGAGAAUUCCUGAGAAGAAGAAUAUGAUGUCUUCCCGGCAAUGGGGACCAAUUUUUCUGAAAGUUUUGCCUGGAGGAAUUUUGCAGAUGUAUUAUGAACAGGGAUUAGAAAAACCAUUUAAAGAGAUACAGCUUGAUCCAUAUUGUAGGCUUUCUGAACCCAAGGUUGAGAACUUCAGUGUAGCAGGAAAAAUCCACACUGUGAAGAUUGAACAUGUGUCUUACACAGAAAAAAGGAAAUACCAUUCUAAGACAGAAGUAGUUCAUGAACCUGACAUAGAGCAGAUGCUGAAGUUGGGGUCCACAUCGUACCAUGACUUCCUUGACUUUCUGACUACUGUGGAGGAGGAGCUGAUGAAGUUGCCAGCUGUUUCAAAACCAAAAAAGAACUACGAGGAGCAAGAAAUUUCCUUGGAAAUUGUGGACAACUUUUGGGGUAAAGUCACAAAAGAAGGAAAAUUUGUUGAAAGUGCUGUGAUAACUCAAAUUUAUUGCCUCUGCUUUGUGAAUGGGAACCUGGAAUGCUUUUUAACCUUGAAUGACCUUGAGUUGCCGAAGCGAGAUGAAUCCUAUUAUGAGAAGGACUCAGAAAAAAAGGGGAUUGAUAUUCUUGACUACCAUUUUCAUAAGUGUGUGAAUGUACAAGAAUUUGAGCAAUCAAGAAUCAUUAAGUUUGUACCUCUGGAUGCCUGCCGGUUUGAGCUGAUGCGUUUCAAGACUUUGUAUAAUGGGGAUAAUCUUCCCUUUUCCUUGAAGUCUGUAGUGGUUGUCCAGGGAGCAUACGUGGAACUUCAGGCUUUUGUCAACAUGGCCUCAUUGGCGCAGAGGUCAUCCUAUGCUGGUUCCUUAAGGUCCUGUGACAAUAUAAGGAUACACUUUCCUGUCCCAUCGCAGUGGAUCAAGGCCCUUUGGACCAUGAACCUCCAGAGGCAGAAGUCUCUGAAAGCUAAAAUGAACCGCCGAGCAUGUCUGGGGAGUUUACAGGAACUUGAAUCUGAACCUGUCAUUCAAGUCACUGUGGGGUCAGCAAAAUAUGAGAGUGCCUACCAGGCAGUGGUAUGGAAGAUAGAUCGGCUUCCAGACAAAAAUUCAAGUCUAGAUCAUCCCCAUUGUCUGUCAUACAAAUUAGAGCUUGGAUCAGACCAAGAAAUUCCCUCUGAUUGGUAUCCAUUUGCUACUGUUCAGUUUUCCGUGCCUGACACCUGUGCCUCAAGGACAGAGGUCAGGUCUCUGGGAGUGGAGAGUGAUGUCCAGCCACAGAAACAUGUUCAGCAGCGAGCUUGCUACAACAUCCAGCCUAAACUCUACAGAUCUGUAAUUGAAGAUGUAAUUGAAGGAGUUCGGAAUCUAUUUGCUGAAGAAGGUAUAGAGGAACAAGUUUUAAAAGACUUGAAGCAGCUCUGGGAAACCAAGGUUUUGCAGUCUAAAGCAACAGAAGACUUCUUCAGAAAUAGCAUCCAAUCACCUCUGUUUACUCUUCAGUUGCCGCACAGCUUGCACCAAACAUUGCAAUCGUCAACAGCAUCAUUAGUUAUUCCUGCUGGUAGAACUCUUCCAAGUUUUACCACAGCAGAACUGGGCACUUCAAACUCCAGUGCAAACUUUACUUUUCCUGGUUAUCCCAUUCAUGUACCAGCAGGUGUGACACUACAGACUGUAUCUGGUCACCUUUAUAAAGUCAAUGUACCAAUUAUGGUGACAGAGACUUCUGGAAGAGCAGGUAUUCUUCAGCAUCCAAUUCAGCAAGUAUUUCAACAGCUUGGCCAGCCUUCAGUAAUACAAACUAGUGUUCCACAAUUGAAUCCAUGGUCUCUUCAAGCAACUACUGAAAAAUCACAGAGAAUUGAAACCGUGCUACAGCAACCCGCAAUUCUACCUUCUGGGCCAGUAGAUAGGAAACACUUAGAAAAUGCCACCAGUGAUAUACUUGUAUCUCCUGGAAAUGAGCAUAAAAUCGUGCCUGAAGCUUUGUUGUGUCAUCAGGAAAGUUCUCACUAUAUCAGUCUUCCAGGUGUUGUAUUUUCUCCACAGGUCUCUCAAACAAAUUCUAAUGUGGAGUCAGUGCUCAGUGGUUCAGCUAGCAUGGCUCAAAAUCUGCAUGAUGAGUCCCUCUCCACAAGCCCUCAUGGGGCUCUCCACCAGCACGUGACUGAUAUUCAGCUUCAUAUUCUUAAAAAUAGGAUGUAUGGAUGUGAUUCUGUAAAGCAACCAAGAAAUAUAGAGGAACCCAGCAACAUACCUGUAUCAGAGAAGGAUUCUAAUUCUCAGGUGGAUUUAAGCAUUCGGGUUACUGAUGAUGAUAUUGGUGAAAUAAUUCAAGUAGAUGGAAGCGGUGAUACAUCUUCCAAUGAAGAAAUAGGAAGUACAAGAGAUGCAGAUGAGAAUGAAUUUCUAGGGAAUAUUGACGGGGGAGAUCUGAAGGUACCUGAAGAAGAAGCUGACAGUAUUUCAAAUGAGGAUUCAGCCACAAACAGUAGUGAUAAUGAAGACCCUCAAGUAAACAUUGUAGAAGAGGACCCUUUAAAUUCUGGAGAUGAUGUUAGUGAACAGGAUGUGCCAGACCUGUUUGACACGGAUAAUGUUAUUGUCUGUCAGUAUGAUAAGAUUCAUCGAAGCAAGAACAAAUGGAAAUUCUAUUUGAAAGAUGGUGUUAUGUGUUUUGGAGGGAGAGACUAUGUAUUUGCAAAAGCCAUUGGUGAUGCAGAGUGGUAAACCUUGUGAGCUCAGUACAUCUAUUUUGUGAACAUCAGUUGGAUUAUAUUGCAUAUUGUGAAUUCAUUUUUAUUUUGAAUAUAGUCCAGCACAGAGCUGUUCAAAUUUUUAGUUCACUGUAUGGAAUUUAAUAAAAUUAUAAUUCAGAUGCAGAUACAAUUA